CCCGCCGCUCCAGACCCCGGAGGAGGGCAGCGCGACCCUCCCCAUCUUGUUACUGGUACUCAGCCACUGGGGACACUGACUGAAUGUUCGCCCCUAACUUACCCGGAAAACACGAGAACUAGUUCGAUGUCGUUUCAACCUUACCAAACUCUGCGGAAACUUAGGAAAUUAUCUUUAGUGUCUAGAUAGGGGAAUUGUUAGAUGGACUUGAAGUCUCUCACCUCCUGUUGUACGCCUCCCGGAAGCAACACCAGGAGUCCAACGGGAUCCCAAACCAGAGCCCAACCAGUAUCCUAUAAAGUCUUCAGAGAGGGAUCCCCUCCAGGCUGGGGAGAAACAGGACAACCUAACAAAACAGGGCCUGGACUCCUCCCUAAACAGACCACGUUUUUCUCCGCUCUUCCCCUUCCCACUCCCUGAAAUCUAGACUAAAACUCUUUUAAGAUAACUGCGAGGUAUAAAGAACGUCUAGAGCCUAAGCGGCCCGUUGCCAGAUUCUACUCCUCAGGCCUCAAAUGUGAGCGCCCCAAACAUUCUAGAGCUGAACCUGGCGGGCAAGGCCCCCGAUCACGUGAUACCGCCCCCCAACUCCGGGCGGAAGAGGCCAGCGACAGCGCUGCACGAAGCGAGUGGGCGGGCGCUCGUGCCCGGCUAAAAGAUGGCUGCUGGCGCCUGGCAGCCACCGCCUGGGAGGUUACUGUAAGGCCCGCAGCUCCCGCCAGCUCCCGCGGACUGCUGCCGCCUCCUUACCAUGAAGCCAGUAAGUCGUCGCACGCUGGACUGGAUUUAUUCAGUGUUGCUGCUUGCCAUCGUUUUAAUCUCCUGGGGCUGCAUCAUCUAUGCUUCGAUGGUGUCUGCAAGACGACAGCUAAGGAAGAAAUACCCAGACAAAAUCUUUGGGACGAAUGAAAAUUUGUAACUCUUCUGGAUUUAAUUAUCUGAAAAUACAGUUCUUUCCCUCAUGCUUAUGUAGAUAUAAAAAUAAAAUUCAUAAUGCAAAGUUCCCAAGUUUA